ACAAGGUAAAAGGAGGCGUGCAGCGAGCAUGAACCGGCUGGGCUGCUGGCCCGCAAGGAGCCUGCCAAGGUCAGGCAGGGGCAGUGGGCAGAGGAGUCUUGGACUUGGGGGCCACCCUUCAGGUCCCAGGCAUCCAGGCACCCCAGCAGCGAAGAGGACAUGGGAGUCCCCUGGUGUGAGGGCCAGAGACUGUCCACUGUCUGUAAGUCUUCUAAGUAGAUGUCAGGGUUCUGGGAGGAGGCCUGCAGGGGGCUGAGGGCCCAGGGGAAGCCCCUCGGACUCCCUCCCACAAGUGGACUCUGCUAUCUGCUUCCUGCUGGGCUGGCCUACACUCAGGCCGUGGGCUGUGGAGAGCUGGGCCGUGGCACAGGCGUGGAGACGACCUUUUUGGCCUGGCCCCGGCCCUUUCCUUCACAUUGUGAGGCAUGGAUUCUUGCUUCUUCUUUUUCCCCACCCCGAGUCUGUGCCACAUCUGCUCUGGGAAGAUGUGGUCUGUGCUUGGCCAUGAAUUCCCAAGGCUUGAAGCAGCAAGGGCUUUGAGGGAGAGGGCCUUGAGGGAGAGGGCCUUGAGGGAGAGGGCUGUGGGGCAGAAGCAGAGAAGGAGAAAUAAGCCUCCGGCCAAGGUCAGGUUGAGCAGGAGAGCCUUGGGUUCUUUGUGGGACAGCACAGAGCUGGGGGUCAGGCGAGCUGUGCCCAGCAAGUAGGCAGCGGCUGGAUGUGACAAAGACCCAGAGGAGAAACACAGAAGAGGGGAGAGGGUCUGGAAGCUGGGGAAAGCAGGAUGGUCGGGAAGGCCUGGCCCCUCACCCAUUCCCAGGGAACGGGGCCUUGGGCCCCAGAAGGGCACAGGCGGGAGGCAGCCGACCCCUGGUGGCAGCGGCAGCAGGCACAGGAGGGCAGAAUGCAGCUGGGGUGUGCGUGGGUGGCAGCAAGGAGGGGCGGAGGGAGGAAGCUGGCUUCCUGGAGCCUUCUCAGCCCUCAAAGACAGACCGACAGACAGACAGACAGCUGGCAAGAGGCAGCCUGGGGGCCACAGCUGCUUCAGCAGACCUCAUGGCUGAGUGAGCCUCCCCUGGGCCCAGCACCCCACCUCAGCAUGGUCCAAGCCCAUGGGGGGCGCUCCAGAGCACAGCCGUUGACCUUGUCUUUGGGGGCAGCCAUGACCCAGCCUCCGCCUGAAAAAACGCCAGCCAAGAAGCAUGUGCGACUGCAGGAGAGGCGGGGCUCCAAUGUGGCUCUGAUGCUGGACGUUCGGUCCCUGGGGGCCGUAGAACCCAUCUGCUCUGUGAACACACCCCGGGAGGUCACCCUACACUUUCUGCGCACUGCUGGACACCCCCUUACCCGCUGGGCCCUUCAGCGCCAGCCACCCAGCCCCAAGCAACUGGAAGAAGAAUUCUUGAAGAUCCCUUCAAACUUUGUCAGCCCCGAAGACCUGGACAUCCCUGGCCACGCCUCCAAGGACCGAUACAAGACCAUCUUGCCAAAUCCCCAGAGCCGUGUCUGUCUAGGCCGGGCACAGAGCCAGGAGGACGGAGAUUACAUCAAUGCCAACUACAUCCGAGGCUAUGACGGGAAGGAGAAGGUCUACAUUGCCACCCAGGGCCCCAUGCCCAACACUGUGUCGGACUUCUGGGAGAUGGUGUGGCAAGAGGAAGUGUCCCUCAUUGUCAUGCUCACUCAGCUCCGAGAGGGCAAGGAGAAAUGUGUCCACUACUGGCCCACAGAAGAGGAAACCUAUGGACCCUUCCAGAUCCGCAUCCAGGACAUGAAAGAGUGCCCAGAAUACACUGUGCGGCAGCUCACCAUCCAGUACCAGGAAGAGCGCCGGUCAGUAAAGCACAUCCUCUUUUCGGCCUGGCCAGACCAUCAGACACCAGAAUCAGCUGGGCCCCUGCUGCGCCUAGUGGCAGAGGUGGAGGAGAGCCCGGAGACAGCCGCCCACCCCGGGCCUAUCGUAGUCCACUGCAGUGCAGGGAUUGGCCGGACGGGCUGCUUCAUCGCCACGCGAAUUGGCUGUCAACAGCUGAAAGCCCGAGGAGAAGUGGACAUUCUGGGUAUUGUGUGCCAACUGCGGCUAGACAGAUUAUUAGAAAGAAGGAAACUUGAGGCUCAGGAGUAUUCCUGGCCCGACCCAAGGCUUCAGAGAUCUGGUUUUGUCCCAGGAGCUGAGUGGAUCAAGGAAGACCAAGUGUCAACAUGGGGCAUCACCCCUCAGCACGUAGGGGGGAUGAUCCAGACGGCAGAGCAGUACCAGUUCCUGCACCACACUUUGGCCCUGUAUGCAGGCCAGCUGCCUGAGGAACCCAGCCCCUGACCCCUGCCACCCUCCGGUGGCCCAGGUGCCUACCUCCCUCAAGCCUGGGAAGGUGGGUCUGGGGAAAGUGGGCCGAGUGAUCUGGGGGUACCCCUUGGGUUGGUGUGGGGAAGGAGUGCCUCCUUAGUGGUGCUUGCAGUCACAGGAAGCAGCAGCAGUAAGGACAAGGGGCCGGAUUCCAGGUCUUCAACACUGGCCACUCCUCUGCUUCCUCUGUUGGCCCCAGAUGGACAGUAAGGGGAACCUCCAAUGUCUCUCUGAACUUAAAGACAGGAGCUGGCAUUUAUGACAGACAAAGAAAGAAGCCCAGGUGUCCUGGUGUUCUCUGAGACACUCUUUGUGAGCUUCAGUUUCCUGUUCUAUAACAUGAACAUAAGUGCUUAGCUGCCAUGAGGGAAAAGUAAUGAGAGAAGUUUCUAGAAGCCACUCCAGCCACUCCUUCCUGGGGCUGACAAAAGGGUGAUUCCAAGAUCAUCCUUCACCCGAGGUCCUGCCCAAGCACAGGCCAGAUGCAAGAAUGGGGAAAAGUCUGGUCCUGAUCUCCAAGUCUCAACAUCCUAUCAGUGACUCUGCUCCCUGACCACACAUCGGAAGGGCUGGAUGACCCCAAUCAAAAGAAAGAACAAGGACUCUGGUUACCCUUGCCUCCACCCAUGUGUCAUAAGAGUAGGCUACAGAGGUGACCAGGCCUGGCAGUUGAAAUCUCUGGAAGAGGGAACAUGUGGGGACUACUCAGAGGCAAAGAGGAGCUGCUCCUGCCUCCAUGGUUGCUGGCCACUCCCACCAACUACUCUUAGGGAGGCUAAGCAGUCUCUGUUUUGCUUCCAUGGCUCAAAUAAUACCCUGGGUAUGCAGGACCCACUAUACCUUGCAUUUGCUGAGUACACCUAGAGAGCUUGGCUGUUUCCAAAAACAAUCAGGGUCAUAACCAUCCAUGCAGACAUGGAGGCUCGGCUGAACCAGGACUCCUCACUGUCUACCUGAGAGAAUGAGCACCCCUCAUCCAUCUCAGCAUCAACACAAUUUCCAGGGGACCUCAGGUCUACCUCAGGACUGAACGCCACACCUCAGGAUUCCUCCUCCUUGAAUCUGAGACUGGCUGCCCAUUCUGAGAUGGGGAUGAAGGUAAGAUGCCGCAUCACCAGGCACGCCGCCCCUGACAGCUGCCUUGAUACCAGCUCUCUGUGGAAACCCCCGAGGAGUUGGAUCUGGAGAACAGCUGGGCCUCCUCACUCAGGACUUCUCUCCUGAAGAACACGCAGUGCUAAAACUGAGGAUGAUUUCCCUAAUGCUUCUGCUUGGCCUUAUGGAGGAGCUGCUCCUUCCUUACAGCCUUGGGGAUGGACUUGCCCACACCUCCACCUCCCCUGAGCCCUGUGAGAGGCACGACUGUCUAUGCCAAUGAGGCUCGGUGGGGGGCUCUCAAGUGCCUGAUCCUGCCCUGGGCUCAGAGCCAGCCCAGAGGGAAGCAACUGCACAGCCCCACAGGCCCUCCCUGGCACUGUCCCCCCAACCCCAUCUCAGAGCUCAGAGGGUACAAGCUCCAGAACAGUAACCAAGUGGGAAAAUAAAGACUUCUUGGAUGACUGACUC